AAAUAUGUUUAAGUUGUACUCAUGAGGAUGAAAAUCACCAAAGUUUUUUCUAUAAGCCUUGUGCAUUUUGUAUGUAUUUGUAUCAAAAGAUAUUUGGAAUUCCUAUUUAGCCAGAGGGCAGUGACUUGAUCCAGUUAUUUGUGGUAACUCUCUUCUUCCCAAUGAUGGAGUAGAGCAUAAAGGAGGGGAGAAAUGGGGCAAGAAAUGACUGACUGUCACUACAAGAUAUGUCUUUGGUGUUUUUUUUGGCUUUGUUCUGUUUUGUUUUGGGGGGGGACAUGGUCUCUCUCUGCCGCCUAGGCUGGAGAGCAGUGGCAUGAUCUCGGCUCACUGCAGCUUCUACUUCCUGGCCUCAAGCAGUCUUUCCACCUCAGCCUCUCAACGCACUGGAAUUACAGAUGUGAGCCACCACACUAGGCCUACAAGUGGUCCUUACACCAGAUUAAUUUAUCUUGAAAUGGCGGGCAACUGAAUCGCACACCUCAAUCUAUGAUUUGACUUUUAAAGAAUUAAUUAUAUUGACUGAGAGAGAGGCCCAGGAGAGAAAGAAGAAAGAAAAGGAGCCAGGGAUGGCUCUUCCUCAGGGAUCUUUGACAUUCAGGGAUGUGGCUGUAGAAUUCUCUCAGGAGGAGUGGAAAUGCCUGGACCCUGUUCAGAAAGCUUUGUACAGGGACGUGAUGUUGGAGAACUACAGGAACCUCGGCUUCCUGGGACUCUGUCUUCCUGACCUGAAUAUUAUCUCCAUGUUGGAGCAAGGGAAAGAGCCCUGGACUGUGGUGAGCCAAGUGAAAAUAGCGAGGAACCCAAACUGUGGGGAAUGCAUGAAAGGCGUGAUCACCGGUAUCUCUCCUAAAUGUGUGAUCAAGGAAUUACCACCAAUACAGAACAGUAACACAGGAGAAAAAUUCCAAGCAGUGAUGUUGGAAGGACAUGAAAGCUAUGACACUGAAAAUUUUUACUUCAGGGAAAUCCGGAAAAAUCUACAGGAAGUUGACUUUCAAUGGAAAGAUGGUGAAAUAAAUUAUAAAGAAGGGCCGAUGACCCAUAAAAACAAUCUUACUGGUCAAAGAGUUCGACAUAGUCAAGGGGACGUAGAAAACAAGCAUAUGGAAAAUCAGCUUAUAUUAAGGUUUCAGUCCGGUCUGGGUGAAUUGCAGAAAUUUCAAACUGCAGAGAAAAUUUAUGGAUGUAAUCAAAUUGAGAGGACAGUUAAUAAUUGUUUUUUAGCUUCACCACUUCAAAGAAUUUUUCCUGGUGUCCAAACCAACAUUUCUAGGAAAUAUGGGAAUGAUUUUUUGCAACUUUCGUUACCUACACAAGACGAGAAAACACAUAUUAGGGAAAAACCUUACAUAGGUAAUGAGUGUGGCAAAGCCUUCAGAGUGUCUUCAAGUCUUAUUAAUCAUCAGAUGAUACAUACUACAGAGAAACCUUACAGAUGCAAUGAGUCUGGUAAAGCCUUUCAUCGGGGCUCACUACUAACAGUACAUCAGAUAGUCCAUACAAGAGGGAAACCAUACCAAUGUGAUGUAUGUGGCAGGAUCUUCAGACAAAAUUCAGAUCUUGUAAAUCACCGGAGAAGUCACACUGGAGACAAACCCUACAUAUGUAAUGAAUGUGGCAAGUCCUUUAGUAAAAGUUCCCACCUUGCAGUUCAUCAGAGAAUUCAUACUGGAGAGAAACCUUACAAAUGUAAUCGAUGUGGGAAGUGCUUUAGUCAAAGUUCCUCUCUUGCAACUCAUCAGACAGUUCAUACUGGAGACAAACCCUACAAAUGUAAUGAAUGUGGCAAAACCUUUAAACGGAACUCAAGCCUCACUGCACAUCAUAUAAUCCAUGCAGGAAAGAAACCAUAUACAUGUGAUGUAUGUGGCAAGGUCUUUUAUCAGAAUUCACAACUUGUAAGGCACCAGAUAAUUCAUACUGGAGAGACACCUUACAAAUGUAAUGAAUGUGGCAAGGUCUUCUUUCAACGUUCACGUCUUGCAGGGCACCGGAGAAUUCAUACUGGAGAGAAACCCUACAAAUGUAAUGAAUGUGGCAAGGUCUUCAGUCAACAUUCACAUCUUGCAGUGCAUCAGAGAGUUCAUACUGGAGAGAAACCUUACAAAUGUAAUGAAUGUGGCAAAGCCUUUAAUUGGGGCUCAUUACUAACUGUACAUCAGAGAAUUCAUACCGGAGAGAAACCUUACAAAUGUAAUGUGUGUGGCAAGGUCUUUAAUUACGGUGGAUACCUUUCGGUUCAUAUGAGAUGUCAUACUGGAGAGAAACCUCUCCAUUGUAAUAAAUGUGGCAUGGUCUUCACUUACUAUUCAUGCCUAGCACGUCAUCAAAGAAUGCAUACCGGAGAGAAACCUUACAAAUGUAAUGUGUGUGGCAAGGUCUUCAUUGACAGUGGAAACCUUUCAAUUCAUAGGCGAAGUCAUACCGGAGAGAAACCUUUCCAGUGUAACGAAUGCGGCAAGGUCUUCAGUUACUACUCAUGCCUAGCACGUCAUCGGAAAAUUCAUACCGGAGAGAAACCUUAUAAAUGUAAUGAUUGUGGCAAAGCCUAUACUCAGCGUUCAAGCCUCACUAAACAUCUGGUAAUUCAUACUGGAGAGAACCCUUACCACUGUAAUGAAUUUGGUGAGGCUUUUAUCCAAAGUUCAAAACUUGCAAGAUAUCACAGAAAUCCUACUGGGGAGAAACCACACAAAUGUAGUGAAUGUGGUAGAACUUUUAGUCAUAAAACAAGUCUGGUGUACCAUCAGAGAAGACAUACUGGAGAGAUGCCAUACAAAUGUAUUGAAUGUGGGAAAGUCUUUAACUCCACUACAACCCUGGCAAGGCAUCGGAGAAUUCAUACUGGAGAGAAACCUUACAAAUGUAAUGAAUGUGGCAAGGUCUUCCGUUAUCGCUCAGGCCUCGCACGUCAUUGGAGUAUUCAUACUGGAGAGAAACCUUACAAAUGUAAUGAGUGUGGCAAAGCCUUUAGAGUUUCCCGAGAGGGUGAACAGACGUCAGCGCCAUGUUUCCUAUAAAGCCUGCAAAAUUACAGAGUCUCGCUCUGUCGCCCAGGCUGGAGUGCAGCGGCGCGAUCUCAGCUCACUUCAAGCUCCACCUCUCGGGUUCUUGCCAUUCUCCUGCCUCAGCCUCCCAAGUCGCUGGGACUAUAGGCGCCCACCACCACGCCUGGCUAAUUUUUUUUGUAUUUUUAGUAGAGACAGGGUUUCACCAUGUUAGCCAGGAUGGUCUCGAUCUCUUCGUGCUCUGCCCACCUCGGCCUCCCAAAGUGCUGGGAUUACAGGUGUGAGCCACCGCUCCCAGCCUCUCUGUACAAAUUUUUUGCCACACAAAUCUGAAAAUACCACCUUGAUUUAUGGAUCCUCCAAGUUUUUCACUGAAGUACAAGGGAACAAAUGUAAAUCUAUAAAUUGGGUUAAAUGAUUUCUAGGAAAGUGUAUAAUAAUAAUAACAAUUAUUUUUUUGAGACAGAGUCUCUGUCACCCAGGCUGGAGUGAAACUGUGUCUCAAAAUAAAUAAAUAAAUAAUAAAUAAAUAAAUAAUAGAAAUGAAGUUUUGCUAUAGUUGAGAAAUUAUAGAAUGCCAUGCUUAUUAUGAUAACCUCAUACAGAAAUUUUUACAGCUUUUUGAAAAAUGGCUUUUUUGUUAUUCAAUUUUUAUAGUCUUAUAAACAUUAAUUUUCACAAGACUAGUGUAAAAAUAUUGUAGACAAUUUGUCUAAGCAGUAUUUCGGAAGCACUUUCAACAGUUAUGUAAAGGGUCCUAUUUAUGCUUGAAGAAAGGACAUGUAUAAGGUUUUUAGCAUGAGGAAAUUAAGUCUUUCUCAACCUAGAAGUCAGGAGUUUCAAGAGUAAACAUUCAGUGUUGAAUUAAAGAAUCUGAAUCUAUUUUUUGAUUGAUUACUGACAUCUUUUAAGCCACACUAUUUGGGCAAGUUGAUAAUAAAGCCUGAGUGCUCCCUUCUUUGGUAUAUGCUGGAAGUUCAAGACAUGCCUGGGUACCUUUACCCUUGCCCUACUCCUUAACCAUAGUCACAACACAUUUUCCUGCUCUCACAAGCCACUUUUGAACCAGCUUGGGAAGUCUCCUGCUCUUUCCAGAGUCUCAUUAUGUAACAAAUAUUCUCAUGAUACUUCACUAUGUGACGUCAUCAGUCCCAGCAUCCAAAUCAAAGUGUGGGUGGGGUUCCACUCUGUUCUAGUGGAGUGGCCACAGUGCUAAUUAACAAAAUAUGCUUUGGGUUGAAUAUAUAAAGUUUCUACUUUACUCACCCUGCAGAAUA